CGUUUCGCUUCGAAGAUUGUUUCAGAAGCGUUGGGCGGGGCGUCCCUGAGAGAAAUUACCAAACAAAUGUUGCAUAGCAUUUUCCCUUGCCUCAGAAAUUUUCAGGAUGCUUUCCUUUUUUUUUUUUUUUUUUGUUUUUGAGACAGAGUCUCACACUCUUGCCUGAGCUGGAGUGCAAUGGCAUGAUCUCGGCUCACUGCAACCUCUGCCUCCCAGAUUCAAGCAAUUCUACUGUCUCAGCCUUCCGAGUAGCUGGGAUUACAGGCGCCCACCACCACGCCCGGCUAAUUUUUUGUAUUUUUUAGUGGAGAUGGGGUUUCACUGUGUUGGCCAGGCUGGUCUUGAACUCCCGACCUCCUCAUCCACCCACCUCAGCCUCCCAGAGCGCAGGGAUUUCAGGCAUGAGCCACUGCGCCCAGCCUCCACUAUUUUUAUGUUUGUAUGGUGACACAUUUGAAGGAGUUGCAAGAUGCCAAAGCUCAUAGGAAUCUGGAAACUGUUCUUCAGGAAGAAACCCAUUAGUUUGGAACUGGAGAAUUCCUUUGCAUCAGAUACUAAAAUGAAAGAACCACUUUUAGGUGGUGAGUGUGACAAGGCAGUGGCAUCACAGCUGGGGCUGCUAGAUGAAAUUAAGACAGAACCCGACAAUGCUCAAGAGUAUUGUCAUAGGCAACAGUCCAGAACUCAGGAGAAUGAACUGAAAAUAAAUGCUGUGUUUUCAGAGAGUGCUUCACAGUUGACUGCAGGCAUUCAGCUUUCUCUGGCAUCAUCUGGCGUGAAUAAAAUGCUUCCUUCAGUUUCAACCACAGCUAUUCAGGUUUCCUGUGCUGGUUGUAAAAAAAUUCUCCAGAAGGGGCAAACUGCUUAUCAGAGGAAAGGAUCUGCUCAACUUUUCUGCUCCAUACCAUGCAUCACUGAAUACAUUUCAUCUGCCAGUUCACCAGUUCCUUCUAAGAGAACUUGUUCAAACUGCUCAAAAGACAUUUUAAAUCCAAAGGAUGUGAUUAGUGUCCAGCUGGAAGACACUACCUCUUGCAAAACUUUUUGCAGCCUAUCUUGUCUUUCAUCAUAUGAAGAAAAAAGAAAACCAUUUGUUACCAUAUGUACUAAUAGCAUUUUGACCAAGUGCAGCAUGUGCCAGAAGACUGCUAUUAUUCAGUAUGAAGUAAAAUACCAAAAUGUGAAACAUAAUCUUUGCAGUAAUGCCUGCCUUUCAAAGUUUCACUCUGCUAACAACUUCAUCAUGAACUGCUGUGAGAACUGUGGCACUUACUGUUACACCAGCUCUAGUCUGUCCCACAUACUUCAGAUGGAAGGACAGUCUCAUUACUUUAAUAGUUCAAAGAGUAUUACAGCAUAUAAGCAGAAACCUGCCAAACCACUUAUAUCUGUUCCUUGCAAACCAUUGAAGCCCUCAGAUGAAAUGAUUGAGACUACGAGUGAUUUGGGGAAGACAGAGCUUUUCUGCUCUAUUAAUUGUUUCUCUGCAUACAGUAAAGCUAAGAUGGAAUCUUCUUCAGUAAGUGUUGUUUCUGUGGUGCAUGAUACUUCAACAGAGCUUCUUUCUCCAAAGAAAGAUACGACUCCAGUUAUAAGCAAUAUAGUGUCAUUGGCAGACACCGAUGUUGCCUUGCCCAUCAUGAACACUGAUGUCUUACAAGAUACAGUUUCUUCAGUAACAGCAACAGCAGAUGUCAUUGUGGAUCUUUCUAAGAGUUCACCUAGUGAACCCAGUAAUGCUGUUGCUAGUAGUAGUACGGAACAGCCAAGCGUUUCACCAUCUUCAUCAGUAUUCAGUCAGCAUGCAAUUGGUUCCAGUACAGAAGUACAAAAAGACAAUAUGAAAUCUAUGAAAAUAAGUGAUGAACUAUGUCACCCAAAAUGUACAUCCAAAGUACAAAAAGUUAAAGCUGUGGAAGAGAGUCAUUUGCAACCCACGGAACUUCUAAUUGGAAAAAAACCCUGGAAAAAUUCAGAAAGCAUGAAAAAAGUGAAAUGCAUUUGAAGUCAUUGGAAUUUUGGAGAGAAUACCAAUUUUGUGAUGGAGCUGUCAGUGACGAUUUAUCUAUUCAUUCGAAACAGAUUGAGGGAAAUAAAAAGUACCUAAAGCUUAUAAUUGAAAAUAUUUUAUUUCUUGGAAAGCAGUGUUUACCCUUAAGAGGAAACGACCAGUCAGUUUCAUCUGUGAAUAAAGGCAAUUUUUUAGAAUUGUUAGAAAUGAGAGCAAAAGAUAAAGGAGAAGAAACAUUUCGACUUAUGAAUUCACAAGUUGACUUCUAUAACAGUACACAAAUUCAAAGUGAUAUUAUCGAAAUAAUAAAGACUGAAAUGUUGCAGGAUAUUGUGAAUGAGAUCAAUGACUCCUCAGCAUUUUCAAUCAUAUGUGAUGAGACAAUCAAUAGUGCCAUGAAAGAACAGCUUUCAAUUUGUGUAAGAUACCCACAAAAAUCAUCAAAGGCUAUCUUAAUUAAGGAAAGAUUCUUGGGUUUUGUUGAUACUGAGGAGAUGACUGGGACCCACUUACAUAGGACUAUCAAAACUUAUCUGCAGCAAAUUGGAGUUGAUAUGGAUAAAAUACAUGGCCAGGCCUAUGAUAGCACCACUAAUUUGAAGAUAAAAUUUAAUAAAAUAGCAGCAGAAUUCAAGAAAGAAGAACCAAGAGCUUUAUACAUACAUUGUUAUGCACACUUUUUGGAUUUAUCAAUAAUUAGGUUUUGUAAAGAAGUAAAAGAACUCCGAAGUGCUCUAAAAACUCUCAGUUCUUUGUUCAACACUAUUUGUAUGUCUGGGGAAAUGUUGGCAAAUUUUCGAAACAUUUAUAGGCUAAGUCAAAACAAAACAUGCAAGAAACAUAUAUCACAAUCAUGUUGGACAGUCCAUGAUCGUACAUUACUAUCUGUGAUUGACAGUCUUCCAGAGAUUAUUGAAACAUUGGAAGUUAUAGCAAGCCAUUCUUCAAAUACAAGUUUCGCCGAUGAAUUGAGUCAUUUGCUGACAUUGGUUUCCAAAUUUGAAUUUGUCUUUUGUUUGAAAUUCCUGUAUCGAGUGCUGAGUGUUACAGGAAUUCUUUCCAAAGAGCUUCAAAAUAAAACCAUAGACAUUUUUUCUUUGUCUUCAAAAAUAGAAGCAAUUUUGGAAUGUUUAUCAUCUGAAAGAAAUGACGUAUACUUUAAAACAAUCUGGGAUGGAACAGAGGAAAUAUGUCAAAAAAUAACCUGUAAAGGUUUUAAAGUUGAAAAACCUUCUCUUCAGAAAAGAAGAAAAAUUCAGAAAUCAGUAGAUCUUGGCAAUUCAGAUAAUAUGUUUUUUCCUACUUCAACAGAAGAACAAUAUAAAAUUAAUAUCUAUUACCAAGGAUUAGAUACUAUAUUACAAAAUUUAAAGUUAUGUUUUUCGGAGUUUGAUUAUUGCAAAAUAAAGCAAAUUUCAGAACUGUUAUUUAAAUGGAAUGAACCAUUAAAUGAAACAACAGCAAAACAUGUUCAGGAAUUUUAUAAACUUGAUGAGGACAUUAUCCCAGAACUUAGAUUUUAUCGACAUUAUGCAAAGCUUAACUUUGUCAUAGAUGAUAGUUGCAUAAACUUCGUCAGUCUCGGCUGUUUGUUUAUUCAGCAUGGUCUUCACAGUAAUAUUCCUUGUCUCUCAAAGCUAUUAUAUAUUGCUUUGUCUUGGCCAAUUACUUCAGCAAGUACUGAGAACUCAUUUUCUACCCUGCCUCGUCUUAAGACAUAUUUAUGUAAUACCAUGGGACAAGAGAAGCUUACUGGCCCAGCCCUAAUGGCUGUUGAGCAGGAGUUGGUAAAUAAACUAAUGGAGCCUGAAAGACUCAAUGAAAUUGUGGAAAAGUUUAUCAGUCAGAUGAAAGAAAUAUAAUACAUGCUCAUUUGAACUUACCUAAAAGACUUGUAUUUCCAUUGGGAUGUUUUCAUUUCAAAAUUGUUCAAAAUUCAAAAGACACAGAACGAUAAACAGUGAAGUCUCCUUCCCUCCUUUAGAACUCAUUUUCUCUUCCCAAAAAGUGUUAUCUUUUCCUUAAAUAUCCCUCUAGAGGUAUUUUUCCUAAGUGGUAUUGUACGGUGUAUACUGUUCUUCAGCUUGUCUUCUCUGUGUAACAUAUUUUUGAGAUUGUCCCAUGUCGUUACAUGAAGAGUUUCUUGAUUCUUGGUCUAUAAUUGCAGAUGUUAUUGUAUGAAUGUACCAUAAUAUAUUUGAGCAGUCCCUGCUGACAUUUUUUUCCUAACCUUUUGCUAUUAUAAAUAAUGAUUCAUUUUAUAACCUUUUAUAUAGGUCACAUUGCACAUGAGUGAGUUUACUGUAAGCUGGAAAUCUAAAGUUAGAAUUACUAGGUUAAGAUAUGUGCAUUUUUACUUUUGAUAGAUAUUGGCAAGUUGCCAUCUAUAAGGAUUGUGCCAGUUUACAGUCCCACCCACAAUGCAUGAGAGUGCCUAUUAAAUCUUUGUAAGUGUUAUCAAAUGUUUUGAUCUUUCCUAAUCUCUUACUUUAAAAAUGGCGUUUUAAUCUCAGUAGAAUUUUGUAUAUUCACUUAAGAAUAAGGUUGGGGACUGGGCGUGGUGGUUCACACCUAUAAUCUCAGCCCUUUGAGGGCCUACACAGGAAGGAAGAUCGCUUGAGGCCACGAGUUCAAGAUGAGGUUGGCAACAUAGUAAGACCUCAUCACUACAAUUUUUUUUUUUUUAAAUUAGUGAAGUGUGGUACUGCACACCCGAAGUCCCAGCUACUUGGGAGGCUGAGGCAGGAGGAUUGCUUAAGCCCAGAAAUUUGAGGCUGCAGUGAGCCAUGAUUGCACCACUAUGCUCCAGAGUCUAGGCAACAGAGUGAGACCUUAUCUCUUUAAAACAAACAAGAAUGAAGUUAGGUAUCUGUUUAUUUGUUUGAGCCAUUUGUAUUUCCUUUUUUGUAGACUGUCCUGUUUAAACGUUAAAAUCACUGCUGUGGUUUUGAUUUAUACAUCUCAGCUGGAUGGCACAAUAAAUUAUUAAGCCAUGUUAUGAAAAUAUAACUAUAUUUAAGUAACCUGCAAAGAAAAGACUAUUUCUUUAUACUUCAAAAAAGUUUUGUUUUUGUUUUGAGAUGGAGUUUUGCUCUUGUUGCCCAGACUGGAGUGCAAUGGUAUGAUCUCGGCUCACUGCAACCUCCGCCUCCCAGGUUCAAGUGAUUGUCCUGCCUCAGCCUCCCAAGUAGCUGGGAUGACAGGCGCACGCCACCACGCCUGGCUAAUUUUUGUAUUUUUAGUAGAGAUGGGGUUUCACCAUGUUAGCCAGGCUGGUCUUGAACUCCUGACGUCAGGUAAUACGCCCACCUGGGCCUCCCAAAGUGCUGGGAUUAUGGCAUAAGCCACCACGCCCAGCCAGAAAAGUUUAAAUAACAAAGAAAAUGUGAUAUUCAAAGAUUUGAAAGAAUUAAGUGGUAUAUAUAUCUAGGCCUGGAAUUUUUUUUUUUUUUUUUUUUUUUUUUGAGACGGAGUCUCGCUCUGUCGCCCAGGCGGGAGUGCUGUGGCGCGAUCUCCGCUCACUGCAAGCUCCGCCUUCCGGGUUCACGCCAUUCUCCUGCCUCAGCCUCCCGAGUAGCUGGGACUACAGGCGCCCGCCACUGUGCCCGGCUAAUUUUUUGUAUUUUUAGUAGAGACGGGGUUUCACCGUGGUCUCGAUCUCCUGACCUCGUGAUCCGCCCGCCUCGGCCUCCCAAAGUGCUGGGAUUACAGGCGUGAGCCACCGCGCCCGGCCUUUUUUUUUUUUUUAAAGACUAUUUCUCUGGCACUUUUCUCCAGCUGUUUCUCCCUUACCCUCUCAUCAAUUUUGAUAACUUGUACUUUUUCUAGGAGAACAUCUAUUUCAUUGAGGCUUUCUUUCAAAUGCAUUUGCCUAGAGUUGUAGAAAAUAUUCUCAGUAUCUUCUAUAUACCUGUUUUACUUUCUUUCUUUCAUUUUUUAAGACGGAGUCUCGCUCUGUUGCCCAGGCUGGAGUGUACGGUGGCGUGAUAUUGGCUCACUGCAACCUCCACCUCGCGGGUUCAAGUGAUUCUCCUGCCUCAGCUUCCCAAGUAUAUGGGAUUACAGGUGCCCACCACCACGCCUGGCUCAUUUUUUUGUAUUUUUAGUAGAGAUGGGGUUUCACCAUGUUGGCCAGGCUGGUCUCGAACUCCUGACCUCAGGUGAUCCACCCACCUUGGCCUCCCAAAGUGCUGGGAUUACAGGCAUAAGCCACCAUGCCCGGCCCUAAUUUAUUGAUUUCCACCUUAAAAAAGAGAAAACAGGCCUGGCGCAGUGGCUCACACUUGUAAUCACAGUACUUUGGGAGGCCGAGGCGGGCAGAUCACUUGAGGUCGGGAGUUCAAGACCAGCCUGACUAACAUGGAGAAACCCCGUCUCUACUAAAACUAUAAAAUUAGCCGGGCGUGGUGGCACAUGCCUGUAAUACCAGCUACUCGGGAGGCUGAGACGGGAGAAUAGCUUGAACCCCAAAGGCUGUGGUUGCAGUGAGCUGAGAUCGUGCAAUUGCACUCUAGUCUGGGCAACAAGAGAGAAACUCCGUUUCAAAAAAGAGAGAAAAUAGGCUGGGGACGGUAGCUCACGCCUAUAAUCCCAACACUUUGGGAGGCUAAGGCAGGCGGAUCACAAGGUCAAGAAUUCAAGACCAGCCUGGCCAACAUGGUGAAACCCCAUCUCUACUAAAAAUACAAAAAAAAUGAGCCAGGUGUGGUGGUGGGUGCCUGUAAUUCCAGCUACUCAGGAGGCUAAGGCAGGAGAAUCACUUGAACCCAGGAGGCAGAGGUUGCAGUGAGCCAAGAUCGUGCCAUUGCACUCCAGCCUGGGCGACAAGAGUGAAACUCCGUCUCAAAAAAAAAAAAAAAAAAGAAAAUAGAAGUUAACUCUAGUAUUGAAUGUGUGUUGCAUAUAUUUUCAUUCUUUUAAUGGAAGUGCUUAAGGCUAUGAACUUUCCUCUAAAGUCAGCUUGGUCAACCAUGUGUUUUUUCAUUUUCAUCAUUUUCUAGCUGUUUUUAGUUGUAGUUUCUAUCUUGUCAUAAAAUCAAGAAGUUGGGCCAGGCAUGGUGGCUCACGCCUGUAAUCCCAGCACUUUGGGAGGCCGAGGUGGGCGGAUCACGAGGUCAGGAGAUCGAGACCAUGGUGAAACCCCGUCUCUACUAAAAAAAAUUAGCCAGGCGCAGUGGUGGGUGCCUGUAGUCCCAGCUACUGGGGAGGCUGAGGCAGGAGAAUGGCGUGAACCCGGGAGGCGGAGCUUGCAGUGAGCCGGGAUCGCACCACAGCACUCCAGCCUGGGCCACAGAGCAAGACUCCAUCUCAAAAAAAAAAUCGAGGUUGGUGUUCUUGUUUUCAUUUUCAAGUGUUUGUUUUCUAUUCUUGUAGUCUAUUAUACAGCCAAUAAUGUAAAAAAUAAACUUACAUUAAGUAUAA